UCUCCGUCUCCUGGCAGCUCCUCCCCCUUGGGUGCAGAGUCAUCAAGCACAUCUCUUCACCCCAGUGACCCUGUGGAAGCGUCCACUAAUAAAGAGUCAAGAAAAAGCUUGGCUUCAUUCCCAACCUACGUUGAAGUUCCGGGACCCUGCGACCCCGAAGACUUGAUCGAUGGAAUCAUUUUUGCCGCCAAUUACCUUGGCUCCACUCAGCUGCUCUCAGACAAAACUCCUUCCAAAAACGUGCGCAUGAUGCAGGCCCAGGAAGCCGUAAGCAGGAUCAAGAUGGCCCAGAAAUUAGCCAAAAGCAGGAAGAAGGCUCCUGAAGGCGAAUCUCAGCCAAUGACUGAAGUGGAUCUCUUCAUUUCUACCCAGAGAAUCAAAGUGCUGAACGCCGACACACAGGAGACAAUGAUGGACCACCCUCUGAGGACCAUUUCCUACAUUGCGGACAUUGGGAACAUCGUUGUGCUGAUGGCCCGCCGGCGGAUGCCUCGCUCCAACUCCCAGGAGAACGUGGAAGCGUCCCACCCAUCCCAGGAUGGGAAAAGGCAGUACAAGAUGAUCUGCCACGUCUUCGAGUCUGAGGAUGCUCAGCUGAUUGCACAGUCCAUCGGACAGGCAUUUAGCGUGGCAUACCAGGAAUUCCUCAGGGCCAAUGGGAUUAACCCCGAAGAUCUCAGCCAGAAGGAGUAUAGUGACCUGCUCAAUACCCAGGACAUGUACAACGAUGACCUGAUCCACUUCUCCAAGUCGGAAAACUGUAAAGAUGUUUUCAUAGAGAAGCAGAAAGGAGAAAUCCUAGGUGUGGUGAUUGUGGAGUCUGGCUGGGGAUCCAUCCUCCCCACCGUGAUCAUUGCCAACAUGAUGCAUGGUGGCCCUGCGGAGAAAUCUGGGAAGCUGAAUAUCGGUGACCAGAUCAUGUCCAUUAAUGGCACCAGCCUGGUGGGCCUGCCUCUGUCCACCUGCCAGAGCAUUAUUAAGGGCUUAAAGAAUCAGUCCCGAGUCAAGCUGAAUAUCGUGAGAUGUCCUCCGGUGACCACCGUGUUAAUCAGAAGACCAGACCUUCGCUACCAGCUCGGUUUCAGCGUCCAGAAUGGAAUUAUCUGCAGCCUCAUGCGAGGGGGAAUAGCUGAGAGAGGAGGCGUCCGUGUGGGGCACCGGAUCAUUGAAAUCAAUGGACAGAGCGUCGUGGCCACCCCCCACGAGAAGAUCGUCCACAUUCUCUCCAAUGCUGUUGGGGAGAUUCAUAUGAAGACAAUGCCAGCCGCGAUGUACAGGCUGCUGACGGCCCAGGAGCAGCCUGUUUACAUCUGACCGCGGCCACACGCGGUGGCAUGCAUGGAGGACUCUCCUCUUCGUGGUUGUGUUUCUCGUGCUGCAUCCCUGUGUCCACUGAGACUUUCCCCUCUCGCGCCCAGCAUUUGGUUUUACACAGGAAGAGAAGAAUCCACAAGGACCUCUUUACUCUCUCCGAUUUGCUUUUUUUUUUUUUUUUUUUUCAAUACCAGGGAAGUUUCGUAUGCACUCCCUUGAGGAUGGAGAGCAGCCAGCACCCACCUGGUACUGACCCAGGACCAUCCUGGAGGGCUUUCUGGGUGUGUCCAGGGGGUGGGCUGUCACUGCUUGAGGGAGAAUCCUCCCUUCCCAGGAGGUGCAGACUUCUUAAAAGGAGCUCGCGGGGCAGCAAAGCAGCUGAUUCAGCAGUGCCUAAAACCCAGUUGCUGAUCCCUGCUCUCUGAGUUUAUCUGUGGGAAUGUGGUAGUACCCAGGGCCAGCCCACGUCAUUAAGGUUAUGCACUGCCUGCCAUGUAGUUGGGGCACCAUACAUUAUUUCUUCCCAGAAUCUCUGAGCCAACCUUAAACCUCUUCUAUUGCUAGUUCUAAUUUCAACGUAUGUGUGUUUUCUAAUACGAGCCUUCUCACCCCAGGAUAAAAGGGGAAAUAACUGCCUUGGGCAAGGACACCAUAGUGUCACAGAGAGCUUGGCAAUUCAUGGGGCAUCUGAAGCUUUACCAGGUUGUCCUCAAGUUAUCAACCAUUAGAUAAACACAGGCAGGUACUGUCUGCUUCUCUCUCUCUCACACACACACACACACACACAGUCCCAUUUGCAUAUCACCCUUCCCUGCUCCCACCACCAGUGAGACAAGCUGAAGAUUAGGCACACAGAUCCCCUGGAAACCCACCUCUCUGGAAGGCCCCUUCCCUGGCAGGUGGCCAGGCAGGCGGGGGCUGCUCAGCCUCAUCCUGAGAGACCUGCCCUCUCUGCGCUGAGGCCCAGCCCCUCCAGCACCACUUUGGCUUAAAGCAUCCUCCUCCUGGACUCCCCUCCCUGCCGAACACACAUCCCAGGAGUCUGGGAAGGAGGGACUGUUCCCAAGAAGGCAAGCUGCAGGUGCAAUUGCGUCUUGUUUUCUGGCCCAAGGCAAGACCAACUUUCUUCUCUGCUCAGGGCCACUAGGCGGAUGUGAUAUUGGAAAGGCCAGAAUAGUACAUAAACCACAAAAUUAAGGAGACAAUAGCAACCUCAAGUUAUGCCUCAGAAUCCCCAGAUGUGGUCCAUAAACACCCUCUUGCUGCCUUGUGGGCCUGAGAGCAUUUUUGGCUGGUGUGGAAUUGUUCCGUGUUUUCAUCAGGUGCCUCAUAUUUAUGCUUCCGUCUCAGUUCAGUGUAGAUGUUUUAGUAAUAUUAUAAUUCUGAGCCAGUUUUUCACUUGGUCCAAAGAGCAUUUUGUGUUCAUGUGAGGUGUGAUUUGGCUUUGCUUUUGUUUUGUUUCAUUCAUGACCUCAGUAGAGACAGGGGAAGAGAAACUAUUAUAUUUUGUAAUUAAUAUAGUCCCUGUUCUCUGCAUCCGAGAUAUUUAUGUUGUGUCUAUGGAAAUAGGAACUCAGUGAGCAAAUGGUGGGUAGCAUGUAUUUAUAGAGAGAAUGGAGGGAUUCUAAGGAGGGAGCAAAGUGACUAUAACAAGAUUAGGGACAAGAGACUUCAACCAGAGAGUUCUGUGAUCAAUUCCCCGAGAUCUCUGCAUCUUCUGAGUUUUCUGCUUAGAAUCAGGGAAGCUCAGUGCUUGACAGGAACGAGCAGUGGCACUCUCAGUUUCACUGUGUUACAAAGGAGCCCUGAGGAAGGGAGGCCGCUGGCUGCCCAGGUGCCCUGGGGGGAAAGGGACUUCUGCUGCUGCAGAGAGUGGCACCCGGUGGGGCCAGGGGCUCUGGGAUGGUCCGUAAAGCUCCCCAGGACUUCUUUGAAGGAUGCUUUACAGAAUGUUUCUGGGAGACCAGCCUCAAGGUCAACCCAUCACAAACGUGAGGACCAGGAAGGAACCAUGGCCAGGGUUCUCCAUUUGCUGUAGAGUAUCUGGUGAUACAGUGAGACACUAAAGAGUCAUCAGCCAGUUCAUCUUUCCUCUGCCAAUAAGAGUGGAUAGAACAGGAAUGAAGUGUUACUGGUGGUAUUUCAGGCAUCAGGAGCCUUGGAAAAUCAUCGUAGGGGCCCAUGCCUGUCUGUCCCUAGGCACCUGGGCAGUGCCACAGAGGCCCGCCCACGACUGGCCAGGGGACAGAACUCCAGUAGUGCAUCCCUGUACAACCUGCACAUAACGGUUAUGUAUGUUCACCUAAAGGAGAGAAUAUACUUUCUAUUCCUAUUGCACAAAAACCUUGUAAACUUUGAGAGGUGCUGAAAAAGCCAAUUCUGCAAGCUCUCCUAGAGGACUGACAUUGUAACAUUAGAGUGAGAAGAUUUCUCUGCCACAUUCUUUUGUGUUAAUCCAGGUGUGUCUUCACACCCAGUGAGUGGAAGUUGCUGGAGCUCGGUACAGGUCCACCCAGCUGAAGUGGGUUCUUUUUCCCACUACCACUGGGGCAAGGGAGUGAGCCUAGGUAUGGUCACCUCAGCAGCCACAGUCUUAAAAGCAAGUCGCUAGAUUUUUUGAAAGUCCCAAGAGAAGUGGUGGUCUUCCCUUCUGUCAUCCCAGUAUAUAUAGUUAUACAUGUAAAUAUCUAAAUACCCCAUGUAAUGGGAAGGCUAUGUACAGGGCAGCCUUCCCAAACGCUGUGAGGGCACAGAGCUGCUGUGGCUGCUCCACCAGGGUGUGCUGGUGGCUCAGCUUUGGGGUUGGACUCCCACGUUCACCUCCCCCUCCUGGUCCAGGCAGAGGCACCAGAACCCAUCCUGCCUUUUCUCCAGUGUGAGCAUUUCAGGGAGCCACCAUCAGCCUUGGGUUCAUGAGAGGAAGAAACCCCCAAAGACCAAUGCCUGGAGCCCACUUCUCCAGCGACACCUUCCCUCGCCAGAGCAGGCUCCUAGGAGUGCAUGGCAGGGGUGCCGGGUCCCUGUGCACGGGUUUGCUUUCUGAACAUUGCCCAUCAACACCGCCUUCAGGGAGUCCCAGAGUAACCUACUACCUCCCCCAUCGCUCCUCUGCCCCCCUCACCCUGUGGGCACCAACACCUCCCGCACACAGAUGAAAACCAUCUACAGAGCCCUUCCCGGGUCCCUCGACCCAGUGGUGUAGCCGUUACCAAUGUUUACAACCAGGGGCCGCCCCUCCUUAGAUGUGUUUACUCGCAUUCACAGGCCACCUGUUGGUUUGAGUUUCAUGUGUCUCCUUCCCUGGCCUAGGUUGACUUGAGCACACAACUCGAUCUUUCUUCCCCUCCAUCAAGGCAGUGUGUGAGGACUGUGUGGGAAUGACAUUUCUUGUACAUACUUAGCACAGCACCUAGAGUAUGAACUUGUACUAUUGUUCUGUAAAGAGGGUGAAAUAGAGCUUAUUGUAAAGUGUCGGGAGAAGUAUAGUAUUGUAUUUGUAACAAUAUCGUUCUUUGUAUACACAAAACUCAAUGAUCUAUAUAUAAAUAUAAAUAAAUAUAUAAAUAAAAUAUAUCUACACGUGAGCCUGGAAUGUGGACACCGCACACCCACUGAAUGUACUUCCUUGACAGUCUGGUCACUGGUCCCUCCCUCCCUCCCUCCUCCGUCCCGUGGCCACAGUCAUCCAGUUUGGGGUUGUGAUGUAUUUACUGUGCUAUCUAUCUUCCUUUAUUUAACUGAACGCUAAUGUCUGUAUAAGAGUUGCUGCAACAAUAAACAAGAACUUCACCUCUUG